GAGAACCAUCCCAGUAACCCGACCGCCGCUGGUCUUCGCUGGACACCAUGAAUCACACUGUCCAAACCUUCUUCUCUCCUGUCAACAGUGGCCAGCCCCCCAACUAUGAGAUGCUCAAGGAGGAGCACGAGGUGGCUGUGCUGGGGGCGCCCCACAACCCUGCUCCCCCGACGUCCACCGUGAUCCACAUCCGCAGCGAGACCUCCGUGCCCGACCAUGUCGUCUGGUCCCUGUUCAACACCCUCUUCAUGAACCCCUGCUGCCUGGGCUUCAUAGCAUUCGCCUACUCCGUGAAGUCUAGGGACAGGAAGAUGGUUGGCGACGUGACCGGGGCCCAGGCCUAUGCCUCCACCGCCAAGUGCCUGAACAUCUGGGCCCUGAUUCUGGGCAUCCUCAUGACCAUUCUGCUCAUCGUCAUCCCAGUGCUGAUCUUCCAGGCCUAUGGAUAGAUCAGGAGGCAUCACUGAGGCCAGGAGCUCUGCCCAUGACCUGUAUCCCACGUACUCCAACUUCCAUUCCUCGCCCUGCCCCCGGAGCCGAGUCCUGUAUCAGCCCUUUAUCCUCACACGCUUUUCUACAAUGGCAUUCAAUAAAGUGCACGUGUUUCUGGU